CGACUGCAAGCGCUGCCACCUGAGGAGCCUGGUAGCCAAGGCAGCGGCAGGCUCAACCCAGAUCUCGCGAGACGGAGCACGCCUCGCGAGAUUUGACCUCUCGUCCCUGAGAGGCGGGUGGGUGUUAGUUCAGAGGGUUAUGGGAGGGCUCUGGCGUCCUGGAUGGAGGUGCGUUCCUUUCUGUGGCUGGCGCUGGAUCCACCCUGGGUCUCCAACCAGGGCUGCAGAGAGGGUAGAGCCGUUUCUUAGGCCAGAGUGGAGUGGGACAGGAGGUGCCGAGAGAGGACUGAGGUGGCUUGGGACAUGGAAGCGCUGCAGCCUUCGAGCCCGGCAUCCAGCAUUGCAGCCGCCGCGGCGGCCUAAGAGCUCGAACCCUUUCACACGCGCGCAGGAGGAGGAGCGGCGGCGGCAGAACAAGACGACCCUCACUUACGUGGCCGCUGUCGCCGUGGGCAUGCUGGGGGCGUCCUACGCUGCCGUACCCCUUUAUCGGCUCUAUUGCCAGACUACUGGACUUGGAGGAUCAGCAGUUGCAGGUCAUGCCUCAGACAAGAUUGAAAACAUGGUGCCUGUUAAAGAUCGAAUCAUUAAAAUUAGCUUUAAUGCAGAUGUGCAUGCAAGUCUCCAGUGGAACUUUAGACCUCAGCAAACAGAAAUAUAUGUGGUGCCAGGAGAGACUGCACUGGCGUUUUACAGAGCUAAGAAUCCUACUGACAAACCAGUAAUUGGAAUUUCUACAUACAAUAUUGUUCCAUUUGAAGCUGGACAGUAUUUCAAUAAAAUACAGUGCUUCUGUUUUGAAGAACAAAGGCUUAAUCCCCAAGAGGAAGUAGAUAUGCCAGUGUUUUUCUACAUUGAUCCUGAAUUUGCUGAAGAUCCAAGAAUGAUUAAAGUUGAUCUUAUCACUCUUUCUUACACUUUUUUUGAAGCAAAGGAAGGGCACAAGUUGCCAGUUCCAGGAUAUAAUUGAAGUCAGCAACUAAGUCUUCCUUCAAAGUUGUGAUUUUUGGGAAAAUCAUAUAUCCUAUCUUCUCAAAGGAGAAAUAUUGUACAAUAAUAUGAAGGCUUAUAUUUUAAAUAAUUAUUUUUUCUCAACUAAUUUUUUUCACUUAAACUUGAGAGAACAAGUUCAGCUUUUAUCAUAAGAAACUCAUAUGCCUAGCUAGAAUAUAUGACUGACUAUUCAAUACCAUACUGAAGAGUUUGAUACUAUUAAAAUAAGCCGCUUUGUUUUUUAAAUAUGCAGGCAUGGGUUCAGCUUAAUUCCAUAAUUCCCUUCCAGAUUAUUAACUCUUCAUACUUACAGCAAUGAAUCUGACAAUGUUUUUCAAAAAUGUAUGCUCAGGGUUAUUUGUUUCAAGUCAUAGGCCAGAACUUCUAACCAUGUUUAUUGUGUCUAAAAGAGUUGGUUGCUAUUUUCCUUCAUUAUGAAUAGUCAGUAUUUUAAAAGCUCAAAGUAGAAGAGGAGUCACUAAGCCCUAACAGCUUGUCCAAAGAUUUAAAUUCUUAUUUCAAAUUUGAUUUGUCCUUUAAGGUUUAGGGCUAUUUUAUAUUCAGAGUUCUGAAUAAUUACUUUGAAACUGUAGUAUCAUAAAAUUGAAAUAAAAUACAUCUACUAGGCUGUUAGCCAAAGCAUCACCAUUACAAGUCCAUGAAUGUUAAAAUGUACAGGUGGGAUUGUGAAGAUUUACUGACAUCAAAAGUUCUUCUGGAAACAAACCUUUGUUAAAAAAAAAAAGUAUUAAAUUGUUUUAAUAGUGAUUUAUUUGUCAUCAAAUGUACAACUUAUUCUAAAUAUUUUCAUUUUCUGUGUUCUAAAUAGAAAUAUUAAGUUGCAGUAAAAAGAGAAAAAAAGGCUAUUUAGCAUUACAAAGAAUCAUAUUUAAAGGCUGCCCAAUGUAGAGUCUAGUGACCUGUUCAGGACACCUGAAAUAUAAUUAAAUGACAAUUAUCAAGGUUUUAACAAUUUAUAAUUCUAAACCAGAGGAUUAUAAAGAAGUGCAAAUUGACUUUUACAUUCAACUUUAGUUAAAUGAAGGCACUCAGUAUUCUUCCUGAAUAAUACAUUCAGUUUCUCACAUUUUAUGCUUUCAUCUAUUCAGAAUUAUUUCAUAGUAAAAUAAUCUACUCUUAUCACAGCUGUGUGACGAUUUCUAAAUGUAGGAAGGCCUGUGAAACAUGACACUGCAGUUAAAUUGGUUGGCCUAAGGACUAAGUAAUUUUUCUUCUGCUGAAGUUUUAAGUGAGUAUUUGUUCCAAACAAGUUCUGUUGAAAUCUCACGCUGUUGUCAGGAAUCAGUGUUAUCCUGGAACUGUUAUUCUAUUUAAUCUUCAUUAUAGCAGAAAUGUGCCACCAUGGCUUUGACAUGUUGGUAGGUAUUGUCUUCCAGGCUUCAAAGCUGCACAGAGUCUACGUUUUAGAGAGUUGGCACCUUUGAUGUGGUAGUGAGCUGAUCAUCCACUUUCUUCUAAAAUAAAGAGAAGAAAAUGGCCAGUAUUCAUCCUGUCCUUCUCUUUCCCCAUUCCUUGAUAACUCUCUUGUCUUUACUGGGAAGCUGGAGAGUCACAGUCUAGUAGAAGAAAGGUAAGAAUGUGCUUCUUCCAUAGGGGAGGGUAUAAGGGGAAUAAAUAAGUUUUGAUAGUUCAUUGGUGACCAUUAAAUAGUAAAUACAUGGGAUUAGUAGUGCUGAAAAUAGGAAAAAUUCAGACCUAUUUGGAGGACUAACGGUAAAUGGGUCUACUGGUACCGGUUAACAAGUAUUAACUGCAUAUGAAAAACAAAUGCCUGAUUUCAGUGCUACUCCUAUUGCUCAUCUAUUUUGUUAGCAUUAAUAUUUCUAUACCAUAAACUACUGUAUUCCCAAGCCUUACUAUUUACAGAUGAGAAAAUCACAAAGAAUGACUCUCAUUAGUGAACAAUGGUUCAGCACAAUUUGAAUGAUUCAGGGGAACUCAUAUUUCAAAGUGUCAGACUCAGAUGGCCCUUAGAAAAUUUAAAUACUAAAUAUGUAAAGUGAUAAUUAUACUGAAAUUAUAUGGAAUAUGGAAUUAAGUUGUAUAAGUUGAAGUCUUUACCUCAGUCACCAUCAUUUUGAGCUCCUUUGUGCUGGUGAGCAUCAAUUUCUUCAUAAAUAGCUCUGAAACAAAGCCAUCACAGCAAAAGGGUUAUGUAUCAAUUUCAAAGUGCUAUUUUGGUUUUUAACUGCCAGCACUGUAAUUAAAAAUUGAGCUGGUUUUGGAGUUCAGGCUACAUAUGAGUAAAAAUAAGUCUCUGCCCUGAAGUGUGUAUUCUAGUUUAUUUAAAUUCUAAUGUUGCACUUCAUUUUUUCUUUUUUUUUGAGACAGAGUCUCACUCUUUUGUCCAGGCUGGAGUGCAAUGGUGCUUUCUUGGCUCACUGCAACCUCUGCCUCCCAGGUUCAAGUGAUUCUCCUGCCUCAGCCCCACGAGUAGCUGGGAUUACAGGGACACACAACCAUGCCCAGCUAAUUUUUUUGUAUUUUAAGUAGAGACAGGGUUUCACCCUGUUGGCCAGGCUGGUUUCAAACUCCUGACCUCAGGUGAUCCACCCGCCUCGGCCUCCCAAAGUGCUGGGAUUACAGGUGUGAGCCACCACACCCGGCCUUAUUGUUGCAAUUCCUAUGUCUCUUAAAAGUAUGUAUUUCAUAGAACCAAUUAAUUUUUUCUUGUGAUUGAAAUGAGAAAUAUGACUCAAAUUUGGACAGUUUAUGUUUUGCUUAAAAAACUCCUCAGUUUCUUCUGGUUUCAAACUUUUUAAAAAAAUAUUAGGACAAGUGCAGUGGCUCACACCUAUAAUCCCAGCACUCUGGGAGGCUGAGGUGGGUGGAUCGCUUGAGUCCAGGAUUUCAAGACCAGUAUGAACAACAUGGCAAAAUACCAUCUCUACAAAAAACAUAAAAAUUAUCAUGUGUGGUGGUACACACCUGUAGUCCCAGGUACUCAGGAAGCUGAGGUCGGAGGAUCACUGGAGCCUAGGAGGCGGAGAUUGCAGUGAGCUGAGAUCGUGCCACUGCACUCCAGCCUGGGCUACAGAGCAAGACUUUCGUCUCAAAAAAAAAAAAAAAAAAUUAAUCUUCCAGCUUAUUUAAACUAUGUGAUUACAGUCCAGACUCCUCAGCCAUCUAUAGCUCAUCACUGUCAUUUCUGUACUUUUUUUAUAUUGUAUUUUUUCAAUGACAUCCUUCAUUCGUUUUUCUUUUUUCUUUUUUUUGAGACAGGGUCACUGUCACCCAGGCUGGAGUGCAGUGGUGCAAUCAUGGCUUAUUGCAGCUUCGACCUCCCAGGUUCAAGUGAUCCUUCCACUUCAGCCUCUCAAAAUGUUGGGAUUAGAGGCAUAAGCCACCAUGCCAGGCCCAUUCAAUUCUUUAUAUGCGUCUUACAUAUGUCUGUAGCUGGAAAAUAUACCUGAAAGCACAACAUUCAUAUAUACAGUAUAGCAAAACAUGGCUGAGGAAAAAUCUCAAAAAUCACAGCGCUAUGAAACCAUGAUCACCAAGUUCAUAAGGCCCCAGAAUGGUGCUACAAUUUUAAUGUUUCCCUAAAAAGUUUGGUCUCAUCUCCCUCAAAACGAUUUCAGUCUUCUUCACUCUCCUCAAACCUCUAAACUCUCUGGUAGAAACUGCAUUCUUAAUACAUUAAAUGUCUUGAUAUGGAAACUUCCUCAUUUUCCCAUCACUAAAUCUUCAAGUUUAUCUUCAUUUGUAUUGUCCAUUAUUUCUGUGAUCCUGUCUAUUCCUGGCUUCUGAAGCACUUGACCCAUUCAGUUAUUCUUCCCUUCCUGAGUCUUCAACCUCUCCUUCUAUGCCAGAUCCUAUUCUUCAACAUUCACAGAUUCUCCAGCAUCUCCCAUGUCUCCCAUUUUAUACAAAGUACAGCCUUUAAUUCCAUCUCUUCUUGUAGUAAAUGCCUUAGUAUCCUCUAGCUACCAACAACCCCUUUUUUUUUUUUUUUUUUGAGAUGGAGUUUCACUCUUGUUGCCCACGCUAGAGUGCAAUAGUGGGAUCUCAGCUCACUGCAGCCUCUACCUCCUGGGUUCAAACGAUUCUCCUAUUCAUCCUCCCGAAUAGUUGGAAUUACAGACACCCGCUACCACGCCUGGCUAAUUUUUGUAUUUUUAGUAGAGACAGGGUUUUGCCAUGUUGGCCAGGCUGGUCUCAAACUCCUGACUUCAGGCGAUCCGCCUGCCUUGGCCUCUCAAAGUGCUGGGAUUAUAGGCGUGAGCCACCGUGCCCGGCCCCAAACCUGUUUUCAUCACUGCUUCAUAUUUAAGUUCUAAGAAGUUAUCUGUACUUACUGUCUCUACUUAAUCUCUCAUGUGCUUUUCAAAUGCACUGAAAUUUGGGUUCUGUCUUCAUCAGUCCAUCAAAGUAGCUUUUACUAAAAUCAUCAAUGAUCUCCAAUCCAUUAUCUAGUUUUCAGUUCUUAUCUUACUUGUCUGCCCCUGGCACUGUUCUUCACAGUUGUACUCGCUCCUUUUUGCUUCCAAAUUACAUUUUCCUCAUCUGGUACUGAGCUCCCUGUUAACUUUCUUUACUCUUGGUUUUAGCAUUUCCAUUUCCUUGAAUGUGCCAGAGCUCUGUCCUCUGGGUCUUUGUACAGGUUGUUCCUUGGGCCUACAAUACUCAUUUCCAAACUUUUCACUUAACUAAGAAUUGCAGGCCUCAGCAUUAAUGCUACCUGAAGCUUUCUCUAAUCCUCAUUUAAAUUAGUUCUGUUACAAACUUUCAAGUUGCCAUAUUCUUUCAUAACAUUAACACAAAUUUUGUAAACAUGUAUUUGGUGGUUUGUCUAAUUUCUGUAUCCAUACUACGUUUAACCUCUGUGAGGACAAGGGAGCAUGUUUCUUGUUCAGAAUUAUAAAUUAGUCCAGUCAUAGUCCCUGGCACAUAAUAUUGAAAUUAGUGAAUCGUGUGUAUCUUCAUAAACAUACUGUUUGUCCUGGUAGAGCAAAAAUUGUCAACCUGGGAUUCAUGGACAACCAAUGAUGUGAAAAAAACCCAGUAAUUUCCUGCAAGAUUCUGUGCUUUUCCUUGGAGGGAAGUCCCUGAAUUUCAUGGGACUUUCAAAAGAACUGAGACAUUCUGACCCCCAGAAAGAAAGACCCACCACAGUGAUAAAAGAGUUCCAAAGCUUCACCUCCAGCUUUUUACUGUCUCUCCCACCGCCAGUAUCUGUGACACUGCCGUAUCAACAUACAGCAAUCUCCUAAUUUGAAUAUAAUCAAGAACUUUUCCACUACCUGUUUGGAUGGAGAAACUGAUUAAAAAAACGUUUCUAGAAAGCAUACCUAGUUAAGUGCCAGUGUCUUAAACCACUAAUAUGAUCAGUGAUAUAUCUACUCUAUCAGGCAGAAUGACUUAGAGAAAUUUCUCAAACCUGAGUUAGGAAAAAAUACAUAGUGGACUCCUAAGUCCCUUAACAUCUGCUCAUAAAUUAAGUCAACCAUUACAUUGAGGGAUUAAACCAGGGACCAGAAUAUCAAAUGUCUACACAUGUCAGCCAAAGAAGAGAUGCAGAGGGUUGGGUGGGGCUGGAAGCAGAUAGGAGGGGUCUCCAGGGACUAUAGGAGUACAAUCAACUUGAGUAAUCACCUGCUUUUUUCCCCAAACCCUGUGUGGAAUGCAGCCAGCUAGCUGGUUUAAACCAGUUCAUGACAGACCUCAGCAAUUUACAGAUGGAUCCCAGUGUACUUUCCUCAUUACCAUGCUAGUAUCUUCACCCUGGGAGAUGCUAUAGCUUCAUUACCAUAACAUGUGACCUGUGUGCUGAAAUAACGACUCACUGCAUCUGCACAACUGCAACCCCUUUCCAUGCAACGACAUACCCUCUUCCCUCUCUAUCACCCCAUAAAACCCUCCUGUCACUUUCCUGCUUUGGAGACUAUGCCCGGUGCUUUAUUUGUGACAAGUAAUAAAACUAUUGCUCAAAGCCUGCAUUCUUGGUUGGUUAUAGUGGCUCAUGCCUAUAAUCCCAGCACUUUGGAAGGCUGAGGCAGGAGGAUUGCUUGAGCCCAGGAGUUCAAAACUAGCCUGGGCAACACAGACCCCCUUCUCUAUAAAAAAGAAAAAAAUUAAAAGGCUAGGCACGGUGGCUUACACCUGUAAUCCCAGCACUUUGGGAGGCUGAGGUGGGUAGAUGAACUUGAGACCAAGAGUUCGAGACCAGCCUGGGCAACGUGGCAAAACCCUGUCUCUACUAAAUAUACAAAAAAAUUAGCCAGGCGUGGUGGCACAUGCUUGUAGUCCCCAGCUACUCAGGAGGCUGAGGCAUGAGAAUUGCCUGAGCCUGGGAGGCAGAAGUUGCAGUGAGCCGAGAUCACCCCCACUAUACUCCAGCCUAAUGACAGAGUGACACUCUGUCUCAAAAAAUUAAAUUAGCCAGGCAUGGUAGCACACCCCAAUAGUCUCAGCUACUCAUGAGGCUGAGUAGGGAGGACUGCUUCAACCUGGGAAGUCAAGGUUGCAGUAAGCCGUGAUCAUGCCACUUUAUUCUAGUUUGAGUGACACAGUGAGACCCUGUCAAGAAAAAAUAAUAAUAACCUGUGUUCUCAUGGAGAGUUGUCUAUUACCAGAUGAAUGAAUCUCAGGUUUUUUUAGGGGUAACAAGUCUGGUACCCCAGAUGAGACCCAGGGUUGAGCCCUGACUUGACCUCCCUUAUAGGCUCCUGGCAGGCAAAGCAGUGGGAUGUGGAAGCAUGCGUGGGCCAACUCACCUCAGUUGCCAAGAAGGAGACUAGAGAAGGGCCUUGGGACCCCUGACCUGGUGUCUAGUGUAGUCCACUGACCAGCACCACAAGACCUCUCUGGGAGAGUAGAAGCGGCUGCCUAGAGCCCAGACCUUUUGCUCGGUGCUGCUUUGAAGCAGCAGCUCCAUGAACUACUAAAAGAGUGGUCUGGGUUUUGAUCAUUAGGAUUCUGGGUUGUCAGGAUUAGGACCUAGGUCAAGGGAUCCAGGAUUGUUGAGAAAAAGAAGUUCCUUCUUUCAGGUCUGGGAGACUGAGAGACAUCGCCAUCGUUUUAACAAGGGGAAUCCCCAACAAAAAGACAAGGAUGCUUGUCUUCAGGCUUUGUUCCCUACGUGGUAUAACUGUAGGGCUCAAUAUUCUUACUUGUCUGUGGCCUGAAUGAAUAUGAAGUCUGGAUUCUUCUACCCUUAGUCUGUGGCAACCCCUAAAAUAUCAGGCUUUGUUUUGCAGCAGUCACAGAAGGACUGCUGUUAGUUUGAUGAGGAGACCCAAGUUUCAAAGGGGGCAGUUUUGGUGGGAUCAUGAUCCCUGGAACCAGAAUGCAGUGAUACAAAGGUUACAUGAACAGUGUGUGUGCUUUCUCUGAGGAAACACCUCACUCACUUGAUUGAUUUACCUACCUCCCCACCACCUGAGCUGGAUCCAGAACUACUUCAUUGUCUCCAUGAGAUCUCCUGGGAGGCUGCCCGGACCGAACAUGAUCCAGGGAAAGGAAAUCCCUGUUAUCCUCUCAGCUUCCCAGGACCUCUGGAUGGCUUUGCAUGGUGGCCAGCAAAGAGGACCAGAAGUAUUCAAGCUGAGUUGUGGGAUUUGUGUCAUCAUUAAUCUCCAGAGUUUGGAAGCCCCUCAGACUGUGUGCAGAGACCGUAGAAUGUCGUGAACUAGGUCUUGGAAGGAGAGCUUGUUAGGGUGCCUCCUCUGGCAAUGGAAACUGCAUAUCCACCCAUGACCAAAAAGCAAAUGAUAUAUUACUGUAAUACAGCCUGGCUCCAGUAUUCCCUAGAUCAGAAGAGAUGGUCUGAAUAUGGGUCACUUACUGCAACUCUCCAAUUGGACUUUUUUUGCAAGAAACAUGGUAAAUGGGAAGAAAUGCCCUAUAUGCAAUGUUUUAUGGCCCUCUAUCAAAACCCUGCCUUGCAGAUGAAAUGCAGAAUAUGUAAAUUGGCCAAAGGGAACUAUAUUGCCAAUUCUAGAAGCCUCUGGAGAGGAAGCAUCAGUCAUGUGGGGGCCUAUAGGGAAGGGAACAAGUAAGAAGAGUCCCUUUACUACCCCCUCCAAGAGAAGUGAGGCCCUCUAACUCUACUCGGGGACUGGAACCUUGGCCAAUACAGGGGCAUAGUCCACCUUCUUGGAAAUGGUACCCUCUGCACCUCCAGGGAAAAGCAAGGGCCCGUUCUGUAUUUGCCAGGCCCUCCAAACUCUGCAGAGCCAGCUGUGGCUCCUGCUAUGGCAAUAGCAGGCCCCUGUUGCACUCUUCUUUGCCAGGGAGCACCACUCAUAGUGGGAACGCAUAUAACCCUGGAGGGUGACUGUUGCCACUCAGAGCAUGCCUGUUGGAGAAAGAGGUUUUGCUCGGGUCUAUGUGUUUUUUAAAACUGUUGACUUGUAUAACUGGAAAUCCCAUAGUAAGGGCUUAUGGGUGAGCCCACGAGAGUUCGUAACUCUCAUAUGGAGAAUAUUCUCCACACAUAACCCUACCUGGCCAGGUGUGCAGACCGUAACAGCAACCCUGCUCACAGCAGAAGAUAAAUCUGCCACCAUGGCCAAAACUAAGGAGGAGGCAGACAAUAUGUGUGCUGAUAACCUGGUGACCUGGCCCGUUGAGGUGUCAGUCCCAAUAGCCAACCCAAACUGGGACCCCAGUGAUAACAAGAAUCAAGAGUGGCUUCAUCAUUAUAGGAAUAUGCUUCUCAGAGGUAUGAGGGAAGCAAGCCAGUCCCUGGUCAAUUGGGGAAAUCUCAGAGAAAUAGAACAAGGCCCUAAUGAAAAUCCAUCAGCAUUCCUAAAUUGAUAAUAAGAAUGCCUCCAGAAUUACACCCCUUGGGACCCAGAUGACCCAAAAGCUGAGUAGUACUUUAAUCUCACUUCAUCUCUCAGCCCCAGAUAUUCAGAGAAAACUCUAAAAAGUGGCAAUAAAUCCACAUACUCCCCCUUUCCAACUGGUAGACAUCUCCUUUAAGGUCUAUAGUAAAGAGAUGUGGCAUCUGAUGAAAAGGAAGACAAGAAGAUGCGGCAGCCCUACAGACUACUUCAGGAAGCCCAGGAAGAAGAUGGCAUGGAUUAGAAAAAUUUCAACUGUAGGUGCCUUUGCAACCUAUCCUGGGAGACCCUAAAACAUAUUUAGUUUUAGUGCCUAGAGAUUUUCACUCCUCUAACAUCUCUGGAUACAGUGUCCCUGGUCAACAUGAAGAAGUUACAGAAGAACGCUUUCUGAUCCUGGCCCCUAAAGAAUUUACUUGUGCUAAGUAAUAAAAUUCCUAUUGAUCAAAA